ACACGUGAUGGGCGCCCACCGAGUGCCAGCACCGCCUCCUCCAGCUCCGCCAAGUAGGUGGGAUCCACUACUUUGCAGAGGAGGAAGCCGUUCAGGCCUCCCUCUGUGCACUUUGCAAAAGCCUCUGCCCUUCCAUCUCGAAUCCCUUGGCGCCGAUCACACUUCCUCUGCCUGGAAACCUGGAGCCGUCUCUCGCGAGACGUCCUCCGCCCUGUAGAAGGCCGUUUCGGUUCUUCGUGCGCGGUAGCCGCCCCACUUGCGGGAUUCCAAGGCCUCAUCGAGUGCGGGUAUCUGGCUGUGGAUUCGCCGCCGUCCUGCUGGACGCCUGGAGGCUCGAACCCCGCCGCCCCCCUACCCCAGGCUUUACUCCCACCCCGGCUUCCGCCCACUGUGCUGCCCUUCCUCGGACCUGGGCUGUCGGGAGAGCUGGAGGUGAGCGCUCUUGGGAGAGCCCAGCCAAUUUAAAGAGUACCCCUGAGAAGACUUUGCGGAGGAAAAUUUAACUGCGGGUACCCGCUGAGUUUAUGGUGCGCCCAGUGUUACCAGAGCUUGUGUUGUGCAUCAGGACUGGGAAAAUUGGCAAGGAGUUACGCUAUAAUGACUCAUAUUUUAUUGAACUUUGGUCAUCAGCCAGGAUUUGUUCUAAGUACUUUAUUGUCACUAACAUAUAUAUUUAUGUCUUCACGGCCACCCCGAGGUGGUUACUGUUAUAUCCACUGUGCAGAUGAGGAAACUAAACUGGCUUAGAGAAGUGAAGGAGUUCACACCCGCGGGCAGGAGUAGACCACCCUCUCCUUGGUGUCCACACCUCGUUUCUUCAGGACUGAAGAGGCAGGCCCUGGAGCUCUGCCUGGGUUGCCUGCACUUGUGGAGGUUCCCAUUCCUCCCUUCCCUCAGUUCCUACCCGCCAUCUGCCUCAGAACACCACAUAAUCUCAUCCUACCCUUUACACCACAAGACCCCCAGGACUCCCAGGCAAUACUCUGCUUUAACUCAGGAAAUUUUAACCUGGCAUUUGGUAAUUGAGAUGUUCACCCUUCCUCAAAAGGACUUCAGGGCUCCCACCACCUGUCUGGGCCCCACCUGCAUGCAGGACCUGGGCAGUAGCCAUGGGGAAGAUCUGGAAGGAGAAUGCUCCAGAAAACUGGACCAGAAGCUGCCAGAGCUCCGUGGAGUGGGUGAUCCUGCCAUGAUCUCCUCUGAUACCUCCUACCUGUCCUCUAGAGGAAGAAUGAUUAAAUGGUUCUGGGAUUCAGCUGAGGAGGGCUACAGGACCUACCACAUGGAUGAGUAUGAUGAGGACAAGAACCCCAGUGGCAUCAUUAACUUGGGCACCAGUGAGAACAAACUCUGCUUUGACCUGCUGUCCUGGCGGCUGAGUCAGCGCGACAUGCAGAGGGUGGAGCCAUCCCUGCUGCAGUAUGCUGACUGGAGGGGACAUCUGUUCCUCCGGGAGGAAGUGGCCAAGUUCCUGUCUUUCUACUGCAAGAGCCCAGUACCCCUCAGACCAGAGAAUGUGGUUGUCCUGAAUGGUGGUGCCUCGCUCUUCUCUGCUCUGGCCACGGUGCUGUGUGAGGCCGGGGAGGCUUUCCUGAUCCCCACCCCUUACUAUGGCGCUAUCACACAGCACGUGUGUCUCUAUGGCAACAUCCGGCUGGCCUAUGUCUACCUGGACAGUGAGUGGCUCCAAAGUUCCAGUCUCUGAGAUCCCUGGGGUUGAUGUAGAAGCCAAGAGCCAGACCCAGAAACAGCAAGGUAGGAACAGAGCAGGGUAGACCUAAGCAUGACACCCAAGAGUGAUGAGGGGGUCUCUGAAGUGAUGGGUUGGGGGUGGAUGGCAGUAAGAGGGAGGGACCCCACCUGCUUUUCCAGAGACUCUUCUGAGGAGGCUGGGGAUUACAGGGGAGGAGAGGCCUGAGAGUUCAUAUGUAUUUUGGGGGGCAAUGGUCACUGAAUGUGGCUGGUGGCUCUGAUGGGUCUUUUUCCAGGUCACUGGGCUAGACACACGCCCCUUCCAGCUCACAGUGGAGAAGCUGGAGAUGGCCCUGAGAGAAGCUCACUCUGAGGUCUGGGGAUCAAAUCAAACCUGAGGCUGGGUGUGGGUGGGUCUGAGCAGGGUCUGGACCCCUCUUCUUGUGACUGAUCUCCUCCCGGGAGUAGGGUUGAUACCCGGUGAUUGGGACAGACAGGUAGGGUGGUAGCACAGAAUUAUUCUGGGAGUCAGGCAGAACCCUGCCCAGGGAGGGUCUUCCCUUUCAAAACAGACUCUCAGACCUCAGUUCACAGAGAAUCAACCAGGGAGCAUCACUAAAGAUACCCCCAUCCCUGAUCCAUCUGAUUAUGAUUCAGUGGGUCAAGUAUGGAGUACAGGAGUCUGUGGUUUUACAAGUCUCCCUGGUAGUUUGAGGGGGCAACCUUGCUCACUGUGGGGGGAGCUGAGGACUCCCAAAGGAGAGCAGAGACCAGUAUUCCAGUGGUUCCUUUCCAGCCUACUUUUCAAAAAUCUACUUAAUUUUUUUUUACUUCUGUCAUGAAAGCUAUACAUACUCACUGUAGGAAUUUUGAAAGUGCAAAAGGCCAACCCAAAAUUCUACCAACAAAGGUAACCUACUGGUAUUUGGGUAUAUUUUUUCUCUGGGCCUUGUCCUCCGCCUUUAUCUGAUGCUGCAGAUGUAAUUCUGUGUUCCGCUUGUUUGCUUCAUGUUGUGUUAUGAACAUGUCCCCCUCAAAUCUCCCUGGGAGCCUUCCAGCGAUCAGCCCCCUUUGACUGUGUGGCUCUGGCCUUGGGGAAGAGCUGAGGGUCUCCUGCCCUAACGGAUGGUUUCAGGGUGUGAAGGUCAAAGGCCUCAUCCUCAUCAGCCCCCAGAACCCUCUGGGUGAUGUAUACUCCCCUGAAGAGCUACAGGAGUACCUGGUAUUUGCCAAGAGGUGAGGCACCCCACACUGGCCCCGACAGAGCGUCUGGGCAGCCUGGGGUUCCAAUGCGGGUUUGGUGCAGGUUUUUCUACUCUCUUGACCCCACUGUGGGCUGCUACUUGCUUGGGCCCUUCCUUGGCAGUGGAGCGGGGAAGCAGGGAUUUGUGGGAUGCCCAUUCCUCUUUAUCUUUCACUCUUUAUAACAAUAGCUAUCAAUUAGCGCACACUCUAGGGGCCAGGCACCAUGCUAAGCACUUUAUGUGCCUCAUACAAUCCUCACAACAAUGCUAUCAUACAAUCCUCACAACAACCCUUUAUGUGCCUCAUACAAUCCUCACAACAACCCUCAUACAAUCCUUACAACAAUCCUUACAACAAUCCUCACAACAACCCUACUGAUGCUGUUAUCACAUCCAGCUCACUGAGCCUUAGAGUGGUCAAGUGAGGGGUGGAUCCAGACUUGAACCUGGGUCUCUCCGACUCGAGCCCUUGUGCAUGACCUUGCCCCUCCAUGGAGGUGCCCGGGAGAUCCUUUUCUCCCCUGCAGUGCUUCAAAAGCUCCUCUGUCACCUGCUCUGUAUGUGUGGCUUUCUGUUUGAAAAAAACAGAAGAAAGAAUGGUGUUCUUGGAAAAACAAGUUUGGUAACCCCGGGCUAGACCCCGGCCCCUCUGGAUUUCUGAUGUAUUACCUCCCCACCCUGUGGGACGCAUCUGCCCUACACACUAAGUCUCUCCUCCCCACCCCUGCCUCACUCCAGGCACAGGCUGCAUGUGAUUGUGGAUGAGGUCUACAUGCUGUCCGUGUUUGAGAAGUCUGUUGGGUACCGCAGUGUCCUAAGCCUGGAAAGGUGAGGCUCCCUGACACAGCUAACUCCCCCAGUCCCUAUUAUCCCACGGAGCCCUGGCCACUUUCUGGCUCAGCCCACAGGGCAUGGCCUGCCCAGAGCAAUUCCAUUUCCACCCAGCUGGUCCCACUGGUCCUCAGAUCUAAUGAGAAGCAGGGACGGUUGGGCUAGAUUAGUGAUUUUCAAGUUGUUCUGUGGAAUUUCUGAGAACUCCAAGAAGAGGCCUCAGGAUCCCUUAAGUUAGGGCUGAGUGGAUGGCAAAUUGGCCUCUUUGCUGUUUCCUUUACCUCCAGAGUCGCUCCAGUUUUAUUCAUUCAUUCAUUUACUCAUUCAUGCUCUCAUUCACUCAGCACCUCUGGAGCCCCUUACACACAGAGUGUGCCAAACACCUCUGGAUAUUUAAAUGUUGGGCUUUUUCAUUAGGUUUACUGUAAGCAAAGCAUUUGUGGCCAAAAUACCUUUGGGAACACUUGGAGCAGAUCAUCCUCAAGGCACACUGGCCCAUGCCUGUAAUCCCAGCACUUUGGGAGGCCAAGGUGGGAGGAUUGCAUGAGCCCAGGAGUUUGAGACCAUCCUGGGCAACAUAGUGAGACUCUGUUUCUACGGGAAAGAAAAAGAAAGUGGGGACCAGAUCAUGUGGGUAGUCUGUGAAUCUCACCUUCAGGGGUUCUAACAGUUCCGGCUGUUUGUUCAGAACCUUCAGCCCAGCCAAGCCCUUUCCAUUAGCCUUCUCUUCUUGUCCUCACAAAGCCUUGAGGAGUUGAUGGAGCAUGGAUUGUGACUCUCAUCUAUUUUUUGGAUUAGGAAACUGAGGCACAGAAAAAAGUGAUUGUCCACGAUCCUUGGUUAGUCAUUAAAAAAAAAAUUAUUGAGCAUCGAUUUCGUGGCAGGCACUGUGCUAAGUGCUGGAGAUACAACAGUGAACAAGAAAGACAUAGACCCUUCUUGUGUAGAACUUUAAUUUCUAGCCAGAAAAACCAUUUUAGCGGCUAAAUGCACAUCCAGCCAUUGGAUUAUGGCCAUCAUGAAUGCUAAAAGGGAGAGUCCAGGGAGCUGUGAGAGGAUCUGUUUAGGGUACCUGAUUGGCCUGGUCCCAGGGGGAGUGGUUAGGGAAAGUCUCUUUGAUGAGUGACAUUUGAGCUAGGCUCUAGAUCAUGGCUGUGUUCUCAUUAAACUUUAUUUACAAGAAACAGGCAGCAGGCUAUGUUUGGCCCGCGGGCUGUCAUUUGCUAACCCCUGCUCUAAAGGAUGCAUGGGAAUGGGUGGUUCAAAGACAUGAAACCAGGGCUUGUCCUGGAACCAAAACUAGAUUCAACCACCCAUCUCUUCAUUUGUUCAACCAAACACAUGUGGGUUUCCAUAGUUCUGUGUUGCCUCUGUUCCCAUGCUGUGCUCU